GCCCGCCCACCCAGCCCAUGGCUCCAGGCCCACCUGGCGAACUGACUCUCAGCCCGCGCCUGGGCUAAGCCUGGCUAGGAGCCGCGCAGGUACUCGAGCAGUGGGCGCCCAGGGUCCGAGUGCUCUGCGCCCAGCGCACCGAGGGAGCCAAGGCCGUCGGGCCGGCGCUUUCAGCUGUCUCUCGCAGCAGCUCAGGGCCGCGCCCCCUGGGCUGGCGUCGUGCCCUAGCCAAGGAGAAGUUUCAGUCACGUGCCAGACUUUUUCUUAAUUACAAACUGAUAGAUGGUCCACAUCUCAACUAACAGUAUUGACGCUGUAAGAGCAUCAGAUUUGAAACAUAUCUGUAUUAAUGAAGAGUGACUGCAUGCAAACGACAAUAUGUCAGGAAAGAAAAAAAGAUCCCAUAGAAAUGUUUCAUUCUGGACAGCUGGUAAAAGUCUGUGCCCCAAUGGUUCGAUAUUCAAAGUUGGCUUUUAGGACACUAGUAAGAAAAUAUAGUUGUGAUCUGUGUUACACACCAAUGAUUGUUGCCGCUGAUUUUGUCAAAUCUAUAAAAGCCAGAGACAGCGAAUUUACCACAAAUCAAGGUGAUUGCCCAUUGAUUGUUCAGUUUGCUGCUAACGAUGCAAGACUUUUAUCUGAUGCUGCUCGUAUAGUCUGUCCUUAUGCGAAUGGAAUAGACAUUAACUGUGGUUGCCCUCAGAGGUGGGCAAUGGCAGAAGGUUAUGGGGCUUGCUUAAUAAACAAGCCAGAGCUUGUUCAAGACAUGGUGAAACAAGUAAGAAAUCAAGUGGAAACCCCUGGAUUUUCAGUUUCUAUUAAAAUAAGGAUCCAUGAUGACCUUAAAAGAACUGUAGAUCUUUGUCAAAAGGCUGAAGCAACAGGAGUUUCAUGGAUUACAGUCCAUGGAAGAACUGCUGAAGAAAGACAUCAGCCAGUGCACUAUGAUUCCAUUAAAAUAAUUAAGGAAAAUAUGUCUAUACCUGUAAUUGCUAAUGGAGACAUCAGAAGCUUAAAGGAAGCAGAAAAUGUGUGGCGGAUUACUGGGACAGAUGGUGUGAAGAAAAAAAUGACACUCCAAUGGGCUGCAGUGGCAACCUUUCUUUAUGCCGAAAUAGGACUCAUUUUAAUCUUCUGCCUACCUUUUAUUCCUCCUCAGAGAUGGCAGAAGAUUUUUUCAUUUAAUGUCUGGGGUAAAAUUGCAACUUUUUGGAACAAGGCUUUCCUUACCAUUAUCAUCCUAUUGAUUGUUCUAUUUCUAGAUGCUGUGAGAGAAGUAAGGAAAUAUUCCUCAGUUCAUACCAUUGAGAAGAGCUCCACCAGCAGACCUGAUGCCUAUGAACACACACAGAUGAAACUUUUUAGGUCUCAAAGAAAUCUUUACAUUUCUGGAUUUUCCCUAUUUUUUUGGCUAGUUUUGAGACGUCUGGUUACGCUUAUUACUCAACUGGCAAAAGAACUGUCAAACAAAGGUGUACUUAAAACUCAAGCAGAAAAUACUAACAAGGCUGCCAAAAAAUUUAUGGAAGAAAACGAAAAACUAAAAAGGAUUUUGAAAAGCCAUGGUAAAGAUGAAGAAUGUGUUUUGGAAGCAGAAAAUAAAAAACUAGUAGAAGACCAGGAGAAACUGAAAACUGAAUUAAGGAAGACUUCAGAUGCCCUUUCUAAGGCACAAAAUGAUGUGAUGGAAAUGAAGAUGCAGUCAGAGAGACUUUCGAAAGAAUAUGAUCAACUCCUGAAAGAACACUCUGAACUUCAGCAUUCCAGUUUUGGUGAAUUUUUAAGCAAAAGAAGCCACAAAAAUGGCAGCAUUGGAAAACAGACUGGUUCUAGAAAAGGAUCGUUUAGAAAGAGGCAACAAGAAAAGACUGUGAACUUUAUAAAAGACACUUGCAAUAUACUGUGUCAAAAUGAUAAUUUUGUUAUGUUAGCCUCUAGAAAAUUUAAGUUCAGAAAAAUGCACUAUGACCGGUUCGUAAUUUUUUUAAUGCCACACAUAGGUUGUAUUGUAAUGGCAUUAUCAAAAUAUUUGAUGAUGUUUCAGAUAUAUUGCAAAGUCUGUAUUCCAGCUCUUAAGAAAAAUAUAAGCAUGUUAAAUACCAUAUUUACAUAUUGAUAAUGUCAUUGGUAUAUGGUGGCUGUUUACCAAUAAAAGGAAAAAAUUCAUUAACCGGUUGCUUCCAAAAUUAGAAGUUUUAAGUUGCAUGAAACCAUUAAUAGCCUUGAAAGCUUUGAUAAGUUUUCAGUAAUAAUAACCUAUUUAAUCAGAUGAUGAUGUGUUUGAAAAUAGUGUUCAAUAUCAGCAAAUUUGUACACAGGGAAUGUAAAUAAGGAUAACUGAUCAGAGUUAUCCACUGUAUUUAUAAGGAAGAGUCGGAAAAAACAAUGACCUUAGUUUUUUUUAAGCCUGAUGAUACUAUGGUUUACUCUAAUAAGAUAGCUAUAUUGAUAAUUAUAUUUUUGUUACUGUGCCCUUGCACAUUUUGGUCUUUUUGUUAAUAUUUUUAUUAAUAACACAUAAUUAGUAACCACUCUACUGUUUCAAGUUAAUCUAGUAAUAGAGCUUACAUAUAUUUGUAUAACUGCUAUACCACUGAACUGAAUUUAUUUUACAACAGUGUAGAAUUCUUGAAAAGUUAACGUAGAAAAUAUCCAAAAAGCAGUAUUUCUAGAAAGUGUCCAAAAAGCAGUAUUUCUUUCCCUUGGUUGUGAGAGUAACUAAUUAUAUAAAUAUUACCUCAAAAAUACAUACACUGGUAUCACACAGUCUUUCUACAAUGUUUCUGUAUUCUGAAAGCUAAAUAUUAAGUACUAUUUUUCCAUUCAAAUAUUCAUUUAGAAUUUCCUUUAGAAGAUGGCAGUGAUUAUAAUAUUAAUAUGAUUUCAUUUGUUCCAGUGUUUAGACAUGAAAUCAUCUUCCUUGUCUCAUGAAAACCUAAAUAUAAAAAAAAGGAAAAUACUGGAGUUUUUAUUUCUCUUGUCUUUGUUACAUCCUCUGUUUAUUAUAAUUUUAGCACCAACUUCACACCUAGCUAAUUUUUUUCAUCAUAAAGUGGAUGAAAUGAGCAAGUACCUAAAAAUUUUAUUUCAGAUAAAAGUCAGGAGUUACUGCUAAAAAACAGACAUGUAGGAGACAUUCAACAGGAGUAUGAAAUGAGAGUUAGACCAUAUGGGCUGACAACACCAUAAAUAACAAGAAAAGGGAGUGCUGAAAUAGGAGAGAACAGAGCAAAUGUUAGCUCAAAGUAUAGACUUAGAAAUAUCAAAGUAAGAGCUAUCUGGAUAAAUAUAUAGAUAUUGAGUGCUUGGAAUCCUAGCCUACUAUGUGAAAAUUAAGUCUAAUGUCAGAAUAACUUACAGAAAAAUAGAAAAUGCACAGCUUUAAAAUGGGCAGAGUUAAAAUCUAUUCCCAGCUUUAUCACUUAUUUAGCCAUGCUAGCCUAGGCCUCUAUUUCCUUGUCUCCAAAAUGAGAAUAAUAAAAUUUAGGUCAGGAUUACUAUAUAAACUAAGAUAAUACAGUGAUUCUCAAAGUUGUUCAGACUGUAUAGUAAGGAGAAAGUCUGGUUGCACUUUGAAGAGCUUGAAGAUUUGAAAGAUUCCCAAAAAAGCAUUUUAAAGUUUACAUUUAAGGGACCUUGGACCUCAACCCUCUCAAGUUUACAAGUCUGAAACUUUAGACAUCAAAAGUUUGAGCAGUUUUUCCAAGGCAACAUUGAUAGUUAGAUUCAGGGCCAGGCUGUAAGUCUAGAAUUUAGAUAUCCUGAUCCCCCAGAUACCGCUCUUCUGGUUAUACACAGACCAGCUAUAAUUUGCUAAACAUAAAAUAUUGCAGUGUAUUAGCCGGCUGUGGCUCCAGAGUCUGUGCCCUUUACCACCGUGCCCAACUGUUUCACAUGCUGUGUUUGGUAGUUUUUCCUAGUACUCUCCUUAAUAAUGGUGGUGUUUAGCAAAUUGUAUUACAUAAAUAAAUAUUUAUUUCAUGGAUUGAGUUAUGUUGCAUAUUAAAUUACUUUCCUUCCCAUUGUCAAUAAUGACUUCUUUAUGUCUUAGGCUGUAUUAUAAAUUCAAACACAGGAAUGUUAUUCUUGCCUUUUUCCAUCAGAAUUACCUAAAGUUUUAUUAGACUUUCCCCCUACUUGCAAAUCUGCCUGGAGGUUCUGGUCUUUAGGAAGUAGCACUUAGCAAGUUCUGGAUAAGCACUCCAGAAUUUGGGAUGAGUUAUCCUUGUUGUUUGUCCAGCUCUAUCUUGGACCCCAGUGCUGCUAAUUAGAUUCAUGCCUUGUUCUUUAGGGCAUAAGUUCCUCUCUUGGCUAUUUUUCCUAGUAUGCUGAGAACUAGGAUUCCCUUUCAGUGACAGAGUCCUGCCCUGGAACCCCAAUCAAGAGCCUAAAGUUUAACUACUCUCUGAGAUAUUAGCCUGAUGCCAGCAGCCUGCCUGGAUCUCUAAAUAUUACCCAUUCUGGGAGUUGUUAGUGGUCUCUGCUUUCCUGCAGUGUCACUCCUGCUUCCUCAUUGGGCCUGCUAGCCACAGCUACUUGGAUGUACCCGAACCUGUUGCCUUGCCCUACCUCUGUGGGCUGGUUCAGUUCUGCAUUCCCAUUCCAGUGUCCACUGCCUUCUCGCUAUCCCUCCCAUCUGUGCGCCACCACCAGCUUAUCCCCAGCCCUGCUAACAUGACAAACUAUUGUGCAUUUGAGUGCCCACUAUACAAUGUGUGAAUAUAACCGUGCUUUUAAGCAUUGACUUUAAUGUCUGGGAUGAUCCGUCUAGAGUCCAUGGAACCCUCCUGUGUUUUUUCAUCCCUUUCUUAGUAAUCUUGGAAAUCCACUUAUGAAAUUCUUUUUCUAACAUUUCUUUGCUGAACGGCAUUUUUAAAAUUACUUUCACGGUGUUUCUUUCCAGUUUGAUCUCUACACAAACACAACUUUAUUACUUGCACCAGAAAUGAUUUCAAACACUUUAGGAACUGUGGUAGGCUUAAUUAUGACUUCCCAAAAGAUAUCCCUAUACCAAUCCCUGGAACCUGGAAAUGUUCUCUUCUAUAGCAAAAGAUAUGAUUAAGUUAAAGUCUUGAGAUGGAGAGAUUAUUCUGGGUAAUCUGGGAGUGCCCUAAAUGCAGCUACAUCUAUGCUUAUAUAGAAGCAAAGGGAGAUAUUACCACACAGAAGAGGAGAAAGCACAGUGACCACAGAGGCAGAGAUUGGAGUGAUGGAGCCGCAGCAAAGGAAUGCUGACAGCCACCAGAAGCUGGAGGAGGCAAAGAACAGAUUCUUCCCCAGAGCCUCUUCCAGCAGGAGCAUGGCCCUACAGAUACCGAUAAAACUGAUAUUGGACUUCCUGGCCUCCAGAACUAUGGGAAUAAAUUUAUUGUUUCAAGCUAUCAAGUUUGUGAUUAUUUGUUACUGCUGCCAUAGUAAAUUAAUACAGGAGCAUGCAGGACAGAUCUGUAAUGGCCUGAACUGAAUUUCAAGGGGUGUGGAAAACAGUUACUCUUUAACACCACUCCGUCUUCCCCAUUAGCCAUUUGGAUAAGUCAAAGAUAGCCUUAGCCAUCUCCUAUCUUAGUUACUUUUCUCCUUCAACUGUAUUUUGCCAUUGUCGUUGCCAUUGCCUCUGCCUAACUGCAAGCCAUCAUCAUCUCUCACAUGGACUAUGACGACCUCCUCAUCUCCCUGUAUCUUCUCUAAUGCUUCUCUCAUAUACAUGCUCUCAGCAGCCACCUGGUUUAAAACAAAAACAAAAAAAACACUAAUCAUGUCAUUCCCUGCUUGUCUUCCCGUUCUUUCCAACUGUCAUUCCCUGCUUGUCUUCCAAUUCUUUCCAACUGCAGUUAAGAUCAAACCACCAAGACCUCACCAGGCUCCCAUCUACUUUUCAGCCUCAACUCAGUCCACCUGCUCUGCCAAUCACACCUGUUUCUUUUUGUUGUUCUUUCCCUAGGAUAUAGAUCCUGGCAUACCUGCAUUCUGAUUCUUCUUGGAACAAGCCAAAUUCUUUCCCCUGUCAGUACGUUUGCAUGUGUAGUACAUGUUGCAUCCCAGGCCUGUCUGCCUUCUUACCCUAUUUUAUUUUCAUCAUAGCACUUACUACCAUCUGAAAUGAUCUCAUUUAUGGUUUGUCUCCUCAGUGAUUAACACAGUUCCUGCACACAGUAAAUCAGUAGUUCUCAACAGGAAGUGAAGAGGUCAUCCUGAGGGGAACAUUUAGCAAUACCUAGAGACAUUUCUGGUUGUCAUAACCAGGGGAAUGCUCCUAGUGGAUAGAAGUCAGGGAGGCUGUUAAACCCAUUCCACAAUGCACAGGACUGGAACAAAGAAUGAUCUCUCACUCAGAAUGUCAGUGUUGCCAAGGUGGAGACAUCCUGCAGUAGAUGCUUGUGGCAGAGGGUACUGGUUGUACCCCAGUAUCCAUUCUUUCAUUCACCUGUGUUAAUACAUGCUCCAGUUUUGUAUUUUUUUUUAUAAACAGCUGUCAAGCAUAAAGAUAACAUUUUCCAUCUCCUUGUAUGUAAGUGGAAAUAGGACUGUCAUGUGGGGCCAGUUUCUUUUUUUUCUUCCUCUGUCCUGCUGCUUGAAACAUAUGCUGCUAUCUUAGAUCAUGAGGUCGAGGCCAUGCAAAGUGGAGCAACAAGGAGCUGUGUCCCUGACGCCAUAAGCACCACACCUGUCCUGAAUUGCUGUGAAUGACACCAGCUAACUACAAUGCAUUGUCUCAACAUCCUAGACAUAAUAAAAAGCCAUAAAUAUGUUUGUCCUAUGCAGCACAAAACCUUUGUAUCUUUGCCUUUUAUGUUGGGAUCUUAAUUAAAAAUUACAUCCUCUACUGUC